AAUGGAAUUAACCUUAUUAAACUUCAGUUGCUUCCUAAGUAAAAUGGGAUAGUUCAUAAUAUUUACCUCGGAAAGUCGGUGAAUGGGAGCGACACACUAAUGCUUGCAGGCUUCAGUAAAUGUUUCCCUGAGUAAGGCCCAAUACACAUGUGGACAAAUACAGGAGUGGCUGAUGUCAUUUCUCCUGCAAGGGCAUUGCUCAGCUGUCCCAGGAGAGUCUAGCCAGGGCAUUUGUCGUGAGCUGCCAGCUUGACUCCCUAGUGUACUCGUCUCUACGCGCCUGUAGUUUGACUCCAUGAUGUAUGAAAAUAAACGCGCUUUGACCAAGGAAAGGCGCCUACGUUGAACGAUUCCAGCCUCAGCUUUAAAUAUCACCUUAGGUGUUCAGAGCUCUGCUUCAUGCGCCAGGCAUCCCCUUCUAGAGUUUGCCGUAAUUUUUCUUUCCGUUGUCAAGUGCUUUGAAGAGAAGUCAUUGUCAUGGACAUGGACCCUUUUCUUCACUGUGUGAUCCCAAACUUCAUCCAAAGCCAAGACUUCUUAGAAGGGCUUCAGAAGGAACUGAUGAACUUGGACUUCCAUGAGAAGUAUAAUGAUUUAUAUAAGUUCCAGCAGUCUGAUGAUUUGAAGAAGAGAAGAGAGCCUCACAUCUCCACUUUAAGGAAAAUUCUGUUUGAAGAUUUCCGGUCCUGGCUUUCUGAUAUUUCUAAAAUUGACCUGGAAUCAACCAUUGACAUGUCCUGUGCUAAAUAUGAAUUCACUGAUGCCCUGCUGUGCCAUGAUGAUGAGCUGGAAGGGCGCCGGAUUGCCUUCAUCCUGUACCUGGUUCCUCCCUGGGACAGGAGCAUGGGUGGUACCCUGGACCUGUACAGCAUUGAUGAACACUUUCAGCCGAAGCAGAUUGUCAAGUCUCUUAUCCCUUCGUGGAACAAACUGGUUUUCUUUGAAGUAUCUCCUGUGUCCUUUCACCAGGUGUCUGAAGUGCUGUCUGAAGAAAAGUCACGUUUGUCUAUAAGUGGCUGGUUUCAUGGUCCAUCAUUGACUCGGCCUCCCAACUACUUUGAACCCCCCAUACCUCGGAGCCCUCACAUCCCACAAGAUCAUGAGAUUUUGUAUGAUUGGAUCAACCCUACUUAUCUGGACAUGGAUUACCAAGUUCAAAUUCAAGAAGAGUUUGAAGAAAGUUCUGAAAUUCUCCUGAAGGAGUUUCUUAAGCCUGAGAAAUUCACGAAAGUCUGUGAGGCCUUGGAGCAUGGACAUGUGGAAUGGAGCAGCCGAGGUCCCCCUAACAAAAGGUUUUAUGAGAAAGCUGAGGAGAGUAAGCUUCCUGAGAUAUUGAAGGAGUGCAUGAAGUUAUUUCGCUCUGAGGCACUAUUCUUGCUGCUCUCCAACUUCACAGGCCUGAAGCUUCAUUUCUUGGCCCCUUCGGAAGAAGAUGAGAUGAAUGAUAAAAAAGAGGCAGAAACCACUGAUAUCACUGAAGAAGGGACUAGCCAUAGUCCUCCUGAGCCAGAGAAUAAUCAGAUGGCCAUCAGCAACAACAGCCAACAGAGCAAUGAGCAGACAGACCCAGAGCCAGAGGAAAAUGAAACAAAGAAAGAAUCAAGUGUUCCCAUGUGCCAAGGGGAACUGAGGCAUUGGAAGACCGGUCACUACACUUUAAUUCAUGACCAUAGCAAGGCUGAAUUUGCCCUAGACUUAAUUCUGUACUGUGGCUGUGAAGGCUGGGAGCCAGAAUAUGGCGGUUUUACUUCUUACAUUGCCAAAGGUGAAGAUGAAGAGCUGCUAACAGUGAAUCCAGAAAGCAAUUCUUUGGCAUUGGUCUACAGAGACAGAGAGACUCUGAAAUUUGUCAAGCAUAUUAACCACCGAAGCCUGGAACAAAAGAAAACCUUCCCAAACAGAACAGGUUUCUGGGACUUUUCAUUCAUCUAUUAUGAAUGACAGCACUGGGCAAAGCUGAACAAAAAUGUGACCCUUCGUAAUUACUGGGAAGUCUGAAAGAGCUAAGCAUGGAGUCAAGGAGAACUACAUGGUAGCUUGCCUGACAGUGUUCUUAAAACUGGUUGUCUUUUACUAGGACUCAUAAUGAUUGUCCUCAACCGAGACCUUGAGCUUGCAGCUAAGUACUUAUCUCUUGAUUAAAAAAAAAAAGUUGGCUUUUUUUUUUUUAACAUUUAGUCCUUUUUCCAUAUUGGCUUCUUCAGUGAAUUUUUAAGUUCAAUUUGUUUUUAUUGAGGUAAAAUAUUUAUAACAUAAAACUGACCAGCUUACCCAUUUUUAAAUAUGCAAUUCAGUGGAUUAAGUACAUUCUCAUUGUUGUCCAGCCAUCACCAUCAUCCAUCUCCAGAAGUUUUCCAUCUUCCCAAAUUCUGUGCCCAUUGAACAAUAACUCCCCACCUCCCCUUCCCCUAGCAACAGCCAUACCUUUUGUCUCUAUCAUCAACUUCACUACUCAUAUUUCUCAUGUAAGUGGAAUCAUACAGUAUUUGUCCUUUUGUGACUGGUUUCACUUAGCAUAAAGUCUUUAAGAUGCAUCCAUGUUUCCAGUGUUUCGGUUUUUUUAGAAAAACUCAUACGUGAUUGCAGCCGGGCAUGGUGGCUCACGCCUGUAAUCCCAGCACUUGGGAGGCCAAGGCAGGCGGAUCACCUGAGGUCAGGAGUUAAAGACCAGCCUGACAAACAUGGAGAAACCCCAUCUCUACUAAAAAUACAAAAUUAGCUGGGCGUGGUGGCACAUGCCUGUAAUCCCAGCUACUCAGGAGGCUGGGGCAGGAGAAUUGGUUGAACCCAGGAGGCGGAGGUUGCAGUGAGCCGAGAUUGUGCCACUGCACUCCAGCCUGGGCAACAAGAGUGAAACUCUGUCUCAAAAAAAAAAAAGAAGAAAAAAACAUAAGUGAUUGCAGAAUUUUGUUCUUCUCAUAAUUUCUGGUUUAGAAAAUUAUGGAGCCUUACAUCCUGAUCAUGCUGGGCCUUAGAAUUCUGACACAGUGAGUCAUCACAUUUCCUCCCACUGCCUGUGGCCUUGUUCCACCAUGACUCUCACAGUACAGUGUAGGCUUAGUGUAGUAUUAUUCCCUUGGAAAGGGUCUGGCCUACCAUCACAUGCCCCAAGAAACUUCUGGUUGGUAAAGAAGAUAGGCUGCUUAUUGCCAUGUGUAGUCACUUCCAAGUGCCCACUGCCUUUCCAUCCUGCAAUUGUGGCCUGUGUAUAAUUAAAUGAUUUUAGCCUCACGUGUUGCUUCUGUUUUCCUAAAUACUGUAGGGUCAACUAUAUAACUAAUUGCUUUUUAUUUUAAGAGACGGAAUGCUAAAACCACAUCAGAAUGCCAAGAGGCUGUGCAUCUUGUUAAUUUUUUUCUUGAACUGUUCCAGGGAGUUACAUCAUAAUUACCUGUGUGUGGGUAUGCAUGGGUGGAUGAAAGAUGCUGUUCUCAUUCCAUCCCAAUAGAGUCUUCUGUUUCCUUUCUCUUUUUUACAUUUAUUUUUAGCUUUUGCAGUAGUGUUUAGUGUGGGUUUUACUAAUUAAUAGAAAAAGCACUGGGCCUUUAAACUUCUUAACUACUCUUCUCUUUCAUCUCCUAAAACUUUUGAGUAUUCAUUCUUUUCUGAAGUUUGCAUUUAAAUGAAAAUGACUUUCGCUUUGGCUUUUAGGUUUAGUUUCAAAAAGGUUUAAUUCUGCACCCUAGCCAGUUAAGAAAUGUUUUAGCAGGUAUGCCCUUGAUAUGGAUAUUUAUAUAUUUUACACAUGUAGUAAUAUUAUUUCUAUAACUUACUGUUAUAAAACACUAAUUUUUAAAUGAUGAGAUAAAAAGAAAUAUCUAGAACUAGUUCUAACAUUGUCUUCCCCUAUGCAUAUGGUAACGAACCAUUUUACACCAUACUAUUUUGGAGACCACAAUUUUUUUUGCGUUUGAGAUGGAGUCUCACUCUGUGGCCCAGGCUGGAGUACAGUGGCAUGAUAUCGGCUCACUGUGACCUCUGUCUCCUGGGUUCAAGCAAUUCUCCUGCCUCAGCCUCCUAAGUAGCUGGGAUUACAGGCACCUGCCUCCAUACCCAGCUAAUUUUUUUAUAUUUUUAGUAGAGACAGGGUUUCACCAUGUUGGCCAGGCUGGAGACCACAAUUUUUUAACCACAGUGUAGCAACACUCAAGUGGGAUUGCGAAUACUGUUACUAAUGGUUAAUGUCACAGCUUGCCUUUUCUAUAUUCCAGCUGACUAAAGGUCAUCUCACUCACUUGCCUUCUGAUGUGUUUUCAUGAGUUGAGGGGAAAGGGUGUCAGUGGCAUAACUUCAGGAAGACCCAGGGAAAAGUGCUUGGGUAGGUGAAACUGUCAUGUGUGCCAAGCUUGGAAAAUAGUUUGAGACUCAUGGCUGUAGGCACCAUCCAAGGCCAAUUUUCCAAUUCUGGAAAGCCAAAUCUGAAUCUUAGAAUACCUCACAAGUGUUAAAAUGUGCUUUUUAGUGUCUCCUUUAUCUCAGUGUGUUUAUGAUCUGUCAACACAUAAUCAUCUUUUAUACACUACAAAAAGGGACUCGGGUGUCUGAGGGGAGAGAAUCCCUAGGAGCCCAACUCUGAUGUUGCUGUCAGUUACAUCAUCUACAGCAGCACCUCUUAGAUUGUGAAGGAUGGUGUAACUUAAAAGAUUGUGUUUCUGCACUGAAGAUAGAUACACAGUGAUAGUGAAGUUUGUUUUCCUUAUAGUACUUCAUUUUGCAUCUUGAUUGCUUUUUAGGGCCUGGGGCCAAUGUCAACAACUCUUAGGUAGCAAAAGAAGAAUUAGAACAUGGGCAUCUUUUUUAUACCUCUUUCAGAUAAAAGCUAUGAUGUUCACCUGUAAAA